GUCCCGGCUCCGCGGGUUCCGUGGGUCGCCCGCGAAAUCUGAUCCGGGAUGCGGCGGCCCAAUCGGAAGGUGGACCGAAAUCCCGCGACAGCAAGAGGCCCGUAGCGACCCGCGGUGCUAAGGAACACAGUGCUUUCAAAAGAAUUGGCGUCCGCUGUUCGCCUCUCCUCCCGGGAGUCUUCUGCCUACUCCCAGAAGAGGAGGGAAGCACAGGUGGGUUUCUUUAGCUCUGCGUCGGAUCCCUGAGAACUUCGAAGCCAUCCUGGCUGAGGCUAAUCUCCGCUGUGCUUCCUCUGCAGUAUGAAGACUUUGGAGACUCAACCGUUAGCUCCGGACUGCUGUCCUUCAGACCAGGACCCAGCUCCAGCCCAUCCUUCUCCCCACGCUUCCCCGAUGAAUAAAAAUGCGGACUCUGAACUGAUGCCACCGCCUCCCGAAAGGGGGGAUCCGCCCCGGUUGUCCCCAGAUCCUGUGGCUGGCUCAGCUGUGUCCCAGGAGCUACGGGAGGGGGACCCAGUUUCUCUCUCCACUCCCCUGGAAACAGAGUUUGGUUCCCCUAGUGAGUUGAGUCCUCGAAUCGAGGAGCAAGAACUUUCUGAAAAUACAAGCCUUCCUGCAGAAGAAGCAAACGGGAGCCUUUCUGAAGAAGAAGCGAACGGGCCAGAGUUGGGGUCUGGAAAAGCCAUGGAAGAUACCUCUGGGGAACCCGCUGCAGAGGACGAGGGAGACACCGCUUGGAACUACAGCUUCUCCCAGCUGCCUCGAUUUCUCAGUGGUUCCUGGUCAGAGUUCAGCACCCAACCUGAGAACUUCUUGAAAGGCUGUAAGUGGGCUCCUGACGGUUCCUGCAUCUUGACCAAUAGUGCUGAUAACAUCUUGCGAAUUUAUAACCUGCCCCCAGAGCUGUACCAUGAGGGGGAGCAGGUGGAAUAUGCAGAAAUGGUCCCUGUCCUUCGAAUGGUGGAAGGUGAUACCAUCUAUGAUUACUGCUGGUAUUCUCUGAUGUCCUCAGCCCAGCCAGACACCUCCUACGUGGCCAGCAGCAGCCGGGAGAACCCGAUUCAUAUCUGGGACGCAUUCACUGGAGAGCUCCGGGCUUCCUUUCGCGCCUACAACCACCUGGAUGAGCUGACGGCAGCCCAUUCGCUCUGCUUCUCCCCGGAUGGCUCCCAGCUCUUCUGUGGCUUCAACCGGACUGUGCGUGUUUUUUCCACGGCCCGGCCUGGCCGAGACUGCGAGGUCCGAGCCACAUUUGCAAAAAAGCAGGGCCAGAGCGGCAUCAUCUCCUGCAUAGCCUUCAGCCCAGCCCAGCCCCUCUAUGCCUGUGGCUCCUACGGCCGCUCCCUGGGUCUGUAUGCCUGGGAUGAUGGCUCCCCUCUCGCCUUGCUGGGAGGGCACCAAGGGGGCAUCACCCACCUCUGCUUUCAUCCCGAUGGCAACCGCUUCUUCUCAGGAGCCCGCAAGGAUGCUGAGCUCCUGUGCUGGGAUCUCCGGCAGUCUGGUUACCCACUGUGGUCCCUGGGUCGAGAGGUGACCACCAAUCAGCGCAUCUACUUCGAUCUGGACCCGACCGGGCAGUUCCUAGUGAGUGGCAGCACGAGCGGGGCUGUCUCUGUGUGGGACACGGACGGGCCUGGCAAUGAUGGGAAGCCGGAGCCCGUGUUGAGUUUUCUGCCCCAGAAGGACUGCACCAAUGGCGUGAGCCUGCACCCUAGCCUGCCUCUCCUGGCCACUGCCUCCGGUCAGCGUGUGUUUCCUGAGCCCACAGAGAGUGGGGACGAAGGAGAGGAGCUGGGCCUUCCCUUGCUCUCCACGCGCCACGUCCACCUUGAAUGUCGGCUUCAGCUCUGGUGGUGUGGGGGGGCGCCAGACUCCAGCAUCCCUGAUGAUCACCAGGGCGAGAAAGGGCAGGGAGGAACGGAGGGAGGUGUGGGUGAGCUGAUAUAAAAAGGUUUUUAUGAUA